GCCACAGCUGCUCUGCCAAUAACAAAGGCACAGCAUUUUCCCUCUGUGCAUCUCCAACAUGGAUGCUUUUCAGGGCAUUUUAAAAUUCUUCCUUAAUCAGAAAACUGUUAUUGGCUACAGCUUCAUGGCUCUGCUGACCGUGGGAAGUGAGCGUCUCUUUUCUGUUGUGGCUUUUAAGUGCCCCUGCAGCACUGAGAAUAUGACCUAUGGGCUGGUUUUCCUCUUUGCUCCUGCCUGGGUGUUACUGAUCCUGGGAUUCUUUCUGAACAAUAGGUCGUGGAGACUCUUCACAGGCUGCUGUGUGAAUCCCAGGAAAAUCUUUCCCAGAGGCCACAGCUGCCGUUUCUUCUACGUCCUCGGCCAGAUCACUCUGAGCUCAUUGGUGGCUCCAGUGAUGUGGCUUUCUGUGGCUCUGCUCAAUGGAACUUUCUAUGAAUGUGCCAUGAGCGGGACGAGAAGUUCAGGACUCCUGGAACUGAUUUGCAAGGGUAAGCCCAAAGAGUGCUGGGAAGAACUUCACAAAGUAUCUUGUGGCAAAACUAGCAUGCUACCUACCGUCAAUGAAGAACUGAAACUCUCCCUUCAGGCCCAGUCUCAGAUUCUAGGAUGGUGCCUGAUUUGUUCAGCGUCUUUCUUCUCUCUGCUCACCACAUGUUAUGCUCGCUGCCGAUCUAAAGUUAGCUACCUUCAGCUGAGUUUUUGGAAGACAUAUGCACAAAAGGAGAAGGAGCAGUUGGAAAAUACAUUUCUGGACUAUGCCAACAAGCUGAGCGAGAGGAACCUGAAAUGUUUUUUUGAAAACAAGAGGCCAGAUCCUUUUCCCAUGCCUACGUUUGCUGCCUGGGAGGCUGCUUCAGAGCUGCAUUCUUUCCACCAAAGCCAGCAACACUAUAGCACCCUCCACAGAGUGGUGGACAAUGGUCUGCAACUUAGCCCUGAGGAUGAUGAGACGACAAUGGUCCUUGUGGGUACUGCCCACAAUAUGUAGCUCAUCCACCAUCAAUGACUCAUGGUGUUGAGUGGCAUGCUCAUUCUGUGAUCCUCCUAACGUAUCACCAGCAACCUGUGUGUCUCUGUAUUUUCUUACAUUUGGAGUAUGUUUACAAGACAAUAACACAAAGGAAACUGCUUUGAAGCUCUCAAGUGGAACAUCAGGAUGUGCUCAAAUUGAUGCUGAGGGGUGACAAAGGUGCUCUUGCAUUGGUGGAGAGGGGCUCAGUAGGCCUAAAUGUUGCUCCAAGAUCUAAGAUUUUAUCAUUCAACAGACAGACUCAUGUGAGAGGGCUCAUCAGUCUCUGUAAAUAUUGGUUGCAGAAUUUAGGGGCAGAAGCAAUGGCUUGUGAGUGAGCAAGUUACUCUUAACAUAGGUUGCCCUACACAGUGGCUCCUGCAGUGUGAUCAGCAGGAGUCUCUGUCCUACAAAUCUACACUUUUAAGGAUGUAUGAAAUUGUGGAAUUCAUUCCCUCAGGAUCUGAAGAUCUCAGUUCUCAAAAAUCACAAGUUGCAAGAAUAUGAUACCUAAAAUUGAAAGUUUUUCACAUGUUUUCACUGUAUACUGAAAAUACUCCCCUGGAAGCAGGGCUGCAUCAUAAUUUUUGUGGGCUUUAUGUACUUUUGCCUUUGCGAACCAUUUCCUACAUUCAAAAUAGUAGUAACAAAUAUAUAUAUAUAUAUAUAUAUAUAUAUAUAUAUAUAUAUAUAUAUAUACACACACACAGAAAUAUAUAUUUAUAACUGCAUUGAUAAAAGGUGAAUAUAUUAGCAUUUUCUUCAACCUAAAAGUUUAUGUAUUUUCUUCUGAUUUUAAAAGAAAUUAAAAACAUUUUAGUGGGCCCUUACAAGUAUUAUGGUCCUUAGGCACAGUGCUUACUAGGCCGUGGGUAUGUCUUAGUGCGUUUGGGCUACUAUAACAAAAUAUCAUAGAUAGGUGGCUUAUACAAAAUAGAAAUUUAUUUCUCACAGUUCUGGAGGCUGGGAAGUCCGAGGUCAGGCUGCCAGCAUGCUCAGGUUCUGGUGAGAGCAAUUUUCCAGGUUGCAAACUGCUUGCUGACUUCUCAGUGUCCUUCCAUGGUGGAAAGUGCAAAUAAGCUCCCUUGAGCAUUUUUAUAAGGCACUAAUCCCAUUCCUGGAGGCUCCACCUUCAUGACCCAAUUACUUCUCAAGGCUCUGCUUCUUAGUACUAUCAGCUUGGGGGUUAAGAUUUCAACAUAUGAAAUUGGGGGAGACACAAACAUUCAGACUAUAGUAGGGUAAAUUGACCUUGGCUAAAGGUCUGGGGACACUGUCCAAAGCAGUACUGGCAUAAAACUGCAUUGCAGUCUUACAUUUAUCAGAAAUAAUGCAAAUCUUGCAUUCUACAAUGUACUAUAUCCAUGUUAGUAUGUACAUAUAUAUGUGUAUGUAUAUAUGUACAUAAAUUCUCCUUAAAUCUCUGAGAAGAAUUGUGCUUUAAAAAAGAACUAUGUUUUGUGCUGUGGCUCAUACCUUACAGUGGUAGUCUAUGUCUCUUAGUUUGAGAAAGCUGAAUAUUAACUUCUUAUUAACAUGAAACAUGAUGGCAAACUGAAUCCUACAAGUAUAGGACCCAGAACAUAUCUAUGUUAUUGUCAUUUACAAGAAGAAAUAUGUAUUUGGUCUUUCUUCCUAUUCCUGGUGCAGAGCUCCUAAAACCUUUGGGACCUCCCAAGUGAUGUGUCUGGUAGUACGCGAAUGAGAUGACUGAUAGUUAGGGGCUUCUGAAUGGCCUCAGAAUAGGGUCUGGUUGCCACGGGAACCAACCAUGUGUUUAGAGGGUUGGAACUUUCAGCCCCACUCCCAGACCUUGGGGAAGGAAGAGGGGCUGAAGGUUGAGUCGAUCACAAAUGGAUAAUGAUUUAAUCAAUCAUGCCUAAGAAUAAAGCUUCCCAUAAAAAUCUAAAGGACAAGGUUCAGAGAGCUUCUGCAUUGCUCAAUACAUGAGGAGUGGUGAGCCCAAAGGGGCCGUGGAAGCUCCGUGCCCCUUCCCCCAAACCUGUUCCUGUGCCUCCAUCUGGCUGUUUCUGAGUUAUAUUAUUUUAUAAUAGACUGAUGAUAGUAAAUAAAGCCCUUUCCUGAGUUCUGUGAGCUACUCUAGCAAAUGGUGAAAUCUGAGAAGGAAAUCAUGGGAACCUCUGCUUUGUAGCCACGUCAGAUAGAAGAUGUGAGUAACUUUGGAACCUACUGCUUGUGACUGGUGUCUGAAGUUGGGGGAGAUCUUAUGGGACUGAGCUCUUAACCUGCUGGGGAUCUGCACUUAAUGCCGAUUAAUGCCAGAAUUGAAUUGUAUGAUAUCCAGUUGGUAUUGGAGAAUUGGCCAGUGUGGGAGAAAACCCACACAGUUGGUGGCAAGGAGUGUUCAGUGUUGAGUGUGAAUGUCAAUAAAAAAAGGUUUGUUUUUUCUACGUACAAUAUCUUUGGGAACUUGGAGGUGCAGGGUCAGACGUCUGUGUGUGUAUGUGGCAGGGACAGAACAGGGAUUAGGGAUGUGAGGGGGUAGAGUUUUCAGAAUAAAGGGAGAGAAAAUUCAGCAAAGAGUUCUCCUUCUUAAUCUUUCUUGACUUAAAGUUUGUCUGCCCUUAAGUGUCUUCUGAGCUGGAAAAAGACAUAUAGGAACUGGCCGAUGCCGAUGCCUCUUUUGCAGUGUGUGAGAGGCUGAAACAGAAGUUCUACAGAAGUAGGUUAGCUGUAAGGAGCUGAGGAUUGAGGAGUCAUAUCUGGGGGAUAUUCCUGCCACCCUCAAGUCCAGGGACUUUCUGCACUCAAAAAACUUACGCUCAUGACAAUGACUGCCUCAUUCAAGAAAACCCAAGCUGACUGGCAAGAAGCCAGCAGCCUGGGUACUUGUUGCUGCAGCUUAGUAAGUAGCAGAAGAGCUCAUCCUCCUCCUCUGGAAGAAGCCACUUAACAGGUUCUCAUCCUGACUCCUAAAUUCCUUAACAGUCCUUUACUCAGGAAUAAAACAAGUCCAAGAAAACUUAUCUGUCCCACAAAUAGUCCUGGAGGCAGUGGAGUAAGAUAGGGAGAGCAAAUUGGUGUCUGCUCUUGAGUAUCUUGAGGGAAUGGGUAUCUAGAGGCAGCAGGAUGAACUGGCUUUGAUAGCAGAGACUUUAAAAUGUGUGGACCAUUAGUUGUCUUUGGAUGUGCUCCCUAGAGGCUGCGCCUGACACAGGGAGCUGUGUAUACAUGAUUUAUUAAAAGGAAAUCCUCUUAGGAGAAACAUAUUAGCAGGAUAAACACAAGAAAGAAUGCAGUUACAAGUGGAGUCUCAAUCAAUCCCAGAGGAAAUUCUGGGACUUCAGCCUCAGCUUGACCUAUGGGGGGGCUCUGGAAUGUCAGAUUUCUCCUGAUCCCAAGUGUGCUCUGGGGCUUCCAUUGCAGCCAAGAGAGAGCAUUCCCCAGAAAACUCCAGGUGAGGAGUCUCCAGUGGCCCAAGGGUGAUCCUCCAGAGGAGGUUACACUGCCGAACUGGGACAUUGGCACCCUGGAUUUGAAUAUCUAGAGAGGGCACCCAAUGGUCAUACUAAUGUUUGCCAUAACAGUCUCUUCUAGGUCUAGACUUGAAGCAUAUGGAAGGGUCCUUGGGCUAGAGCCAACCCAAGCCCAGGCUGACUCCCUUUUAAUACUUCUAAUUUUCCCUGAAGAUCUGGUCUUCUCCCUACCACCACUACCCUAUUACAUAAGAGAAAAGGAUUGGAGAAUGCUCUUGAAAAGAAUGUGAUGCUUUCCCAUACAAGGAAUAUACUCAAGGAAAAAUUUCAUGGCACAAAAUGCUGAUUCUGUCCAAUUUAUCCCAUGAAUAAAUUGUGUACACAUAUAUAUAUGAUUCUUUUGUUUUUCCUGUGCAGUUCCUUCCUUUUUUCAGGCUCAACCACUUAAUUCAGCUUUAGGAUACAUUCAGCUUAUUCAUAUCAAAUAUAAAGUGGGAGAAAAAAAGGUAUGUAACAAAGAUUACAAAAAUAAGGCAUGGCAGACAAAUCACUACAUAAUUCUAUGCAUUAUACCUUAAAGUAAUGUAUUGUAAAAUAUAUGUGUCCAAAGCAACUUUUAAAAUUUUUGUAUGGUUUUCUACUUGAGACCUUUAAAGCAUCACUAAAAAUGUAUACAUUUAAUGAGAAAACGAUGACAUUAUUGAUUCAAAUUAGUUGUUUCAAAGCCUGAUGAUCCACUGAUUUACUCUAAAAACUGGUUAAAGCAAUCCAGAAGUCACUGGGUAGCAGAAAACUGCUACCGCUUCUCACAUGAUAUAUUUCAAGUACUUCAACUAUUAACUAUAUUAUUCUAUUUAGACUUUGGUGGUUCCGAAUUCUCUAAGGUAAUUAUCUUAAUUUUCUAAUAUUUCCCUCUCAUUUUUCUCUCUUAUUUUAAAUAUCCCCUGUUGUACAAGCCAGAGGAUAUUAAUUUCCUUUGUGGGUAGUGCUUGGACUUCUCUGAUUUUAGAUCCCAAAAUCAUUAAGAAAAAGCUAAGAGGUUGGCAUGAGAGGUUGGAUGGAAAGCAUCUAUCUGUGUUUGUCAGUAGCUCUCGAUGUUGGCUGCAAAUUGGAAUCACCUGGGGGCCUUUGACAAUCACAAUGUCUGGACCCAUUUCCUGAGAACCUGAUGUAACUUUUCUGGGUUAGGGCCUGAACAUUGAGAUUUCUUUUAAAAGCUUUCUAAGUGAUUAUAAUGUGCAGUCAUGGUGAAGAACUACUGAUUUUAUAUGGGGAGUCAGUGAAGGUGGUGAGGGGCUGUGAGGUUGAAAUAUUGGAAAUGUUAUCUGGAUUUCAAACAGUAGAGUAUGAUAAAAAUUUAAAAACUGGCUCUCCAGGAAAAAAGAGACAUCCUAAUAUGAUGUAUUUGCCAAUAUACCAUGGGUUUUCUUGGGCUGGGAUGAACUUUCAGAAGUUUUACAGUGAGCAUUUUUUUUUUUAUGAAUUUAAAUUGGUUCUAGCUAAGCAAUUUUGGAGUAUCUUUGAUGUACCUGGGUCUCUCAUUUUAAUAAACAUAACAGUGGUAUGUUAGUCAGGGUUCUCCAGAGAAACAGAACCAACAGUACAACAGUAUAUAUACAUACAUACAUAUAUAUGUGUGUGCAUGUGUGUGUGUGUAUGCGUGUAUAUAUAUAUAUGCUACAUAUAUGAAAGGGGAUUUCUUGUGGGAAUAUAUAUUAUAUAUAACAAAACAUGACAAAUAUAUAACAAAAUAUAUGUGCUAUAUAUAUUGUGUGUGUAUAUAUAUAUGAAAGAGGAUUUAUUGUGGAAAUUGGCUCAUGUGAUUAUGAAGGCUGAGAAGGCCCAUGACGUGCCACCUGUAAGCUGGAGAAUCAGGGAAAUGUGUAGGGUGGCUCAAGUCCCAGUCUGAGGGCCUGAGAACCAGGGGAGUUGAUGGUACAAAUCCCAGAGCCAAAGGCAAAGGAACCUGAAGUUUUUAUUUCCAAGGGCCAAUAGAUAAGGAGAAUAUUGGUGACCCAACUCCAGGAGACAGAGAAAAGAUUGGUGACCCAACUCGAGUGGAGAGAGAGGGAGAGAGAGAGAGACAGAGAGCAAAUUUGCCCAUCCUCUCCCUUUUUGUCCUACCCAGGCCCUCAAUGGAUUGUAUGGUGCCUGCCCAGGUUAGGUGAGGGCAGAUUUUCCUUACUCAGUCCACUGAUUCAAAUGCCAAUCUUUUUUGGAAACACCCCUACAUACAUACCCAGAAAUAAUGCUUUAAUAACUAUCUGGCUACCCCUUAAUCCAAUCAAGUUGACAUCUAAAAUUAACCAGCACAUGUGAUAAAUUAAAUAUGGUUCAAUGGCUCCUUCUGGCAGAUGUAGUCGUGUUAUCCUCACUUUGAAUCUGACCUUAUGAACCAAUAAAAUAUGGCAGACAUGAGGUAGAUUGUUAAGCAGUAUCACAGUUUAUGCCUUGGUCUCUUACAAUGUUGCAAUGCUCAACAGUCUGGUAAAAGCCACUAUGUAAGAACUGCAAUUACUCAGGGACUACCAAGCUCUGAAGAGGCCCAAGCUAGCCAGUGGGAGGAGAGAGAGAGAGAUAAAAAGAGAGAGAGAGAGAGAUCCCAAUGGCUCCAAUUGUCUCAGAUAUUCUAGCUUAGGGGUCAGGCAUGUGAAUGAAGGAGCCAUUUUAAACAUUCAGGCCCCAGUGUACACGACAUGGAGAAGAACCAGGAAGUCCAACCAACAGUGAGAAUAAAAGGCCCCAGAUCUAUGGCCCUAAUCAAAUCAUUGCAGCCAUCUCCAAACAUUUGACCCACUCCAGUGGAGGCUGCAGGCUUUGUAGAGAAGUCCUUGCCAUGUCCUAUCCAACUCCAUGACCCCAAAAAUCAUGAGCUUAAAUAAAUGUUUGUGGCUUUAAGCCACUGAAUUUUGGGGCAAUAUGAAGCGACAGAACCUGAACACUAACAUGAAAAUCAGAAUUUAUAAAAAGACAAAAAUUACAGGCAAAUUGUAUUUAUACAUUUAUACAUUCUCCCUAUGCAUAGAGAGCAUUUUCUUCAAUCAUGUUUUCUUUUUCUUUAGGUUCCAGUUAGCAGUAUAGCAUCUACAGCAUGAUUUGAUAGAUGCUGAUAAGUAGGUCUCUAAAAUCUCUCCACCAAAGCUGGAGAUUCACUUUCAAUUAUUUUUGGUUAAUUUUUGUUUGAAAGGAAUACAAACAUAUUAUUGGGAGGAGUAACACAUUAAACUAUUAUUUGUCAUUAAUAUCUACGAAAAAAUAGCAAGUGAGGGUUUCAGACUAGGCUGGCCUUCAGUAAGCUGGAAAGAGAUUGUUCUUCUAGUCGUCUCUCAAAAUGUUAUCUUCAGACUGUCAACAUCAGUAUCACGAUGAAGCUUGUUAGAAAUGCAGAAUCAGACAGUAUCUAAAACCUGUUGAGUCAAGCCUGCAGUUUAACGUGAUCCUAGCUGAUUCCAGUUCAAGCUAAAUUUGAUAACACUAAGGCAGUGGUUCUCAAACUUUAGUCCAUAUAAAAAUCAUCUGGAGGGCUUAUUAAAAUGUGGAUUGCUGAACUCCACCCCCAGGGUGUCUGAUUCAGUAGGUCUGGGGUGAGGCAAGAUAAUCUGCAUUUCUAACAGGUUCUCAGGUGAUACUGAUGCUGCUGGUCUAGGGACUACAUCUUGAAAAUAACUGCUCUACAGCACAGAGCAGGCUAUUCUGGGGAAGGCAGGCUGUAAGAAACUCAGAAUCCUGGCCUGCACUCCAGAUCUACUGAAUCGGUCAUCAGCCCGUCCAAGAUUUUGGGGUGCCUUUCCAUUCAUUCAAGGAUACCUUUCUAUUCAUUCAAGGAUAUAUUUUGUCCUUUAGGAAUAUUUUAAAGUUUACUUCACAUAAGUUUUACAUGUUUCUUGUAAACUCUAUUUGUAGGUGUUUUCUUUGUUCCUGUUGUAAAUGGUUUCUUUUUUCCACUAUAUCUUUCUAAGUGAUUGUUGUCUGAGUACGUGAAAAGCUAUUGUCUUAUGCUUAUUAAUUUUAUCUCUCUACUAAUUCUUUUAUUGUUUGUAGGGCUUUUCAGAAUUUGAAAGUAAACAUUUUGCAACCUUUGAUGACAAAAUGGAUCUAGACAAUAAAUAAUGAAUUCUAAACUAUUAGGUGAAAGCAGAAUGGGGUCAGACCUAUGCAAUUUGAAGCCACUCAUCUAUAUUAGCAUCACUAAAAAUCAAAGCAGAUGCUACGUGCCUUAUGAUGCAAGGCAAGAAUAAGUACAUAGUAUCACAUGUGAAAUAUUGUUUCCUAAGAAGCUAAACCUAAUCAAGUAUUUAGACAUUACUGCUAGUUUAUAGGAAACAUAAGCAACAAAAAACAAGGCAAUUAGCACCACAAAAAAACAACCAGGUACAUCUAGAUCUAACAGAACAUUCCAUUUUACAGAUGACUCAGUCUCCCCACAGAUUAACAGUAUUAAGAAAGGAGAAUAAAGGAGAUAUAAGUGACUUAAUAACCAGAUAUGCUAUAUAGACCUUAUUUGUAUCCUGUUUCCAACAACCAACUGUAACAAGAUAUCUUUGAGAUAUUUAGGAAAAUAUGAAUGAAUAUUAGAUGAUUUUUAGAGAAUUAUUAAUUUUGCUAUGUGUGGUAAUGGUGUGCCGAUUUAUGUUUUUUAAAAAGUUCUUCAGUUAGAGAUGUAUAUUUAAAUAUUUAUGUGUGAACUGCCAUGAUGUCUAGAAGUUUCUUUAAAAUACUCUAGAAAAAAGAGUUUAGGGAGAAAGCUGAAAGAUGAAAUAAGAUUGGCAAAAUAUGGAAACUAUUGAAGCUGGAUGGUAGGUACACGGAAUUCAUUACAUUAUUCUCUUUACAUUUGUAUAUGUUUGAAAAAUUUCAUAAGGUACACAACAAAAUAAAUGACAUGGUCACCUCAGUUAUUUUGCUGAAGUUUUGUCAAUCACCCCCUGCUUAGCUGGAGUUUACCUUCUAGUAUCAUUCUCAGCAAAGGCUCACAGGAAUGCUAUUCUCUGAAUUCUUACAUAUUCAGCCUGUUGGCCUGUUCUCGAAUUGAAGGACAGCUUGUCUGGUUCAUACUUUCUCUACAUGAGUGUAUUGUAAGCAUUACUUCAUUGUCUUUUGUCAUUGAAUAUUGCUGAGGUGGCCACAGCCUGAUUUCUGAUGCCAUCUCUAUUUCUUUCUUUAUUACUAACAAGAUGUUUUAUCCUAUAUUCUCAUUGGUUUCUUUAUCUUUCAUGUCCAAAAAUGUUAAAUAGGCCUUCAGGUAGGUCUUUUUGGAACGAUUUUUCCUGCUACAAGUUUACUCUUUCAUUGUGGAGAAUCAUUUUCUUAUAUUUCAAUAAAAAAGUUGGAAAAUUUUCAA